CGUCGAAGCCAAAGAAGACCAGAGCCAGCCGGGUGGCACAGCGGUGUCGUGGCCGUGUUGCUGAUCGCCUGGGUGGUUGUUGGCGUGUCCCUGCAGCGAAGGAUCCUGGUUGACAGUGAAAAAGCAGUCUGGCUCCCGAGGUCCACCCCUUAUACCCCAAGGUCCAGAUGGCGGCCAACGUGGGUGAUCAACGUAGCACAGAUUGGUCUUCUCAGUACAGCAUGGUGGCUGGGGCAGGCCGAGAGAAUGGCAUGGAGACGCCGAUGCACGAGAACCCGGAGUGGGAGAAGGCCCGUCAGGCCCUGGCCAGCAUCAGCAAGUCAGGAGCUGCCGGCGGCUCUGCCAAGUCCAGCAGCAAUGGGCCUGUGGCCAGUGCACAGUACGUGUCCCAGGCAGAAGCCUCAGCUUUGCAGCAGCAGCAGUACUACCAGUGGUACCAGCAGUACAACUAUGCCUACCCCUACAGCUACUACUAUCCCAUGAGCAUGUACCAGAGCUAUGGCUCCCCUUCCCAGUAUGGGAUGGCCGGCUCCUAUGGCUCAGCCACACCCCAGCAGCCAUCCGCACCCCAACACCAAGGGACUCUGAACCAGCCCCCAGUCCCCGGCAUGGAUGAGAGCAUGUCCUACCAGGCUCCCCCUCAGCAGCUGCCGUCGGCUCAGCCCCCUCAGCCCUCAAAUCCCCCACAUGGGGCUCACACGCUGAACAGUGGCCCUCAGCCUGGGACAGCUCCAGCCACACAGCACAGCCAGGCGGGGCCCGCCACGGGCCAGGCCUAUGGGCCACACACCUACACCGAACCUGCCAAGCCCAAGAAGGGCCAACAGCUGUGGAACCGCAUGAAACCCGCCCCUGGGACUGGAGGUCUCAAGUUCAACAUCCAGAAGCGACCCUUUGCUGUUACCACCCAGAGCUUUGGCUCCAACGCAGAGGGCCAGCACAGUGGUUUUGGCCCCCAGCCCAACCCUGAGAAAGUUCAGAACCACAGCGGGUCCUCUGCCCGGGGGAACCUGUCUGGGAAGCCGGAUGACUGGCCCCAGGACAUGAAAGAGUAUGUGGAGCGCUGCUUCACCGCCUGUGAGUCGGAGGAGGACAAGGACCGCACGGAAAAGCUGCUCAAGGAGGUGCUGCAGGCGCGGCUGCAGGACGGCUCGGCCUAUACCAUUGACUGGAGCCGGGAGCCCUUGCCGGGGCUGACCCGGGAGCCUGUGGCUGAGAGCCCUAAGAAGAAGCGGUGGGAGGCCGCUAGCAGCCUUCACCCUCCUAGAGGGGCAGGCUCGGCGACAAGGGGCGGGGGUGCCCCGUCCCAGCGAGGGACGCCCGGGGCUGGGGGUGCCGGUCGAGCCCGGGGCAACAGCUUCACCAAGUUUGGCAACCGCAACGUCUUCAUGAAGGACAACAGCUCUUCUUCCAGCACAGACUCCCGCUCCCGCUCCUCCUCCAGGUCCCCGACGCGCCACUUCCGCAGAAGUGACUCCCACUCAGACUCCGACAGCUCCUACUCAGGGAAUGAGUGUCACCCUGUGGGCCGCAGGAACCCGCCCCCUAAGGGCCGGGGCGGUCGAGGGGCCCAUAUGGAUCGGGGCCGAGGCAGGGCGCAGCGUGGGAAGAGGCACGAUCUGGCGCCCACCAAGCGCAGUCGAAAGAAGAUGGCGGCGCUGGAGUGUGAGGACCCGGAGCGAGAGCUGAAGAAGCAGAAGCGGGCAGCCCGCUUCCAGCACGGACACUCCCGCCGCCUGCGCCUCGAGCCCCUGGUGCUGCAGAUGAGCAGCCUGGAGAGCAGUGGGGCUGACCCUGACUGGCAGGAGCUGCAGAUCGUGGGCACCUGCCCUGACAUCACCAAGCACUACCUGCGCCUCACCUGUGCCCCCGACCCGUCCACCGUGCGCCCUGUGGCAGUUUUGAAAAAGUCGCUGUGCAUGGUCAAGUGCCACUGGAAAGAGAAGCAGGACUACGCGUUUGCCUGCGAGCAGAUGAAGUCGAUCCGGCAGGAUCUGACGGUGCAGGGCAUCCGCACCGAGUUCACGGUGGAGGUGUACGAGACCCAUGCCCGGAUCGCCUUGGAGAAGGGUGACCAUGAAGAGUUUAACCAGUGCCAGACGCAGCUCAAGUCGCUGUACGCCGAGAACUUGCCUGGCAAUGUGGGCGAGUUUACUGCCUACCGAAUCCUCUACUACAUCUUCACCAAGAACUCGGGAGACAUCACCACGGAGCUGGCAUACCUCACACGAGAACUGAAGGCAGAUCCUUGCGUGGCCCACGCCUUGGCAUUAAGGACAGCCUGGGCCCUGGGCAACUACCACCGCUUUUUCCGGCUCUACUGCCAUGCACCCUGCAUGUCUGGCUACCUCGUGGACAAGUUUGCAGAUCGGGAGCGCAAGGUCGCCCUCAAGGCCAUGAUCAAAACGUAUGUGGUGCCAAGCUCCCUUCUGCCUUUGCUCUUCCCAUCCUUCCGCCUCGCACCGCCCCUCAGACCAGCUCCUGGCCGCAGGCCUCCCCCAGCCCCCAACCCUUGUCCUGGUCCUUGCUUCCCCAUCAUCUUUCUCCAUUCAGCCCUCCCCUCUCCAGUUCCUCUUGCUCUCCUUGUUGGUCACCUCUGUGUUCCGGGUCACUCCUCUCCCUCUCCCCACUGUUCCCAGCUCACUGCCUCUGGGGCCUCUUCUCCACCCCAUCUGUGUGUCUCUUCCUCCUGUUCUCUCCUGCCUGGACCCCCUAGUUCACUCCUUGCCCUGGGCUUCCUCAGAACCCUGAGGUCUCUGCUUUCUCAGCUUGUCGCUGUGCUCCCACCAUAGAGACCAUCUAGACAGCCUCUGGUCUACCAGGACAAGGCCCAGUCCCACUCAGCUCCUUUGAGAGCACCAGAAACGCUUAGGGAGACACCUGUGUUGAGGCCACACUGGGCGCGGUGCCAGAGGCCCCUGGUCAGGCCAUGCCCCUGCAGUGUCCUUCGUUCACUAGACAUUGCGCCUGGCUUGCUGUGGGUGGGGAUGAGUUGCUUGACUCAUGUUUAGACGCAUGGUUCUGUCUGGUGAUUGAGGUGCCCAGGCGACGCUGGGCAAUGUCAAGAGAGGUUUUCGCUUGUCACAGCAAGGGGAUGCUCUUGGCAUCUAGUGAGUGGAGGCCAGGGAUGCUGCCCUGCCACUGCCAUUGGGCCUCAGAGCUCAGUCUUGCCAAGGUGGAGAAAUUCUGGUCGAAGAGGUUGACCGGUAGACUGAAGAGGCCUUGAGAGCCUGGCCAGGUGGCUGUCCACGUGAGGUCAUAGUCACAGCAUGGAGGCCUUGAGAGCCUGGCCAGGUGGCCCUCCACGUGAGGUCAUGGUCACAGCAUGGGGGCCUUGAGUGCCUGGCCAGGUGGCCCUCCACGUGAGGUCAUGGUCACAGCAUGGAGGCCUUGAGAGCCUGGCCAGGUGGCCCUCCACGUGAGGUUGUGGUCACAGCAUGGGGGCCUUGAGAGCCUGGCCAGGUGGCCCUCCACGUGAGGUCAUGGUCACAGCAUGGAGGCCUUGAGAGCCUGGCCAGGUGGCCCUCCGUGUGAGGUCAUGGUCACAGCAUAGUUUGGAGCUAGGGAGGGACUGUCAGCCUGGAGGUUUGGAGACUCAUUCUGGAAUCUAGUGUGGGUCAAGCCAACUUCAGGGAGAGGCUGAGCCAGGGUAGGAGUCACAGGAGCAGACGAGGAUGUGGGGUGCCGUGCACAGAGCUCCAUGACCAGCUUGGGAAGUUAGAAGGAAGGGGAGGCAGGAGGCUGCUUAGUCUGCUGCCAUGAUGGGCCCCAUGAAUGGUGGCUCUCAAGCUUCUGUGCUACACAGGGGUGUGUGGUUGGGCGAGUGUCCUUGUUAAUUGAUACCUAAUUGGCCUUGGUUGGGAACAUAGCCAUGAGUGCCCCUCGUGGGUGGGGCGCCAGUCUGUCAUUGACCUCAUUGUGUCAGCACCUUCCCCCCAAGGAGGCUGACCCUGCCCUGCCAGCUGAGACUGGGAGACGGAGUGGGCUCUGAUCCCAGGGCUUCCAGGAAAGCUCUGGCUUUGGAGCAGAAGCGGGUUCUAGGACUUAGUGCCCCUCACUCGGUGCCUGGGUUCCUGUGUGUGUGGAAAGGGUAGGGCUGCACCCUGUGGAAGAGGGUUCAGGGAGCUCUGAGGACCUGGCUCGUGCUAGAUGCUCAGUCAGUAGUGUGUUUUAGCAGCAGCCGGAAGUGACUGCUUUCAGUGUGUAGUGGUGAGUGCUAGCUGGCACCCCUGCGCCUGGCUUCCCAGACACUGUAACGCAGGGCAGGGGAGGCAGCGAGGGCUGGGUCCCCACGGUGGCCCUGGCAGCCCCGCCAUCCCCAUCCCCUGCCACGUGCUGCUCCCUCCAUCUGGUCCCUGCCCCUCAGCCAGCGGAGGAGCCCGCUGGGCCCUUCCCUGCCCGUCCCCGCUCCUCCCUGGCCCCCGCACAGGUAAGUGAGGGUGAGGGGGGCACAGGGGACUGGGGUCACUAACCCCCCCCGGGCCCCCCCCGAGCCCCUGAGGUGGGGAGGCUGGGAGGCGGGUGGGGAGCCAGCAGGCACUGUGCUGAGGAAAUCCUGUGGGCACCCGAAUGGGGGGGCCUCCCCGCUCGUGGGGCCCUCCCCUGCCCUCCCGCCCGCCCGCCUCAUCACCUUCUCCUCUUGUCUCCAUAGCUUCCGCCCUGCGCUGCCAGUCUCCUACCUGCAGGCCGAGCUGGCCUUCGAGGGCGAGGCCGCCUGCCGGGCCUUCCUAGAGCCCCUGGGCCUGGCCUACACGGGCCCGGACAACUCCAGCAUCGACUGCCGCCUCAGCCUGGCGCAGCUGUCAGCCUUCUGAGCACCCAGCGAGGAGGGGCGGGGGCAGGGGCUGCAGCCCCCAGCGCUGCCUUUGCGGAUUCUGUUUUUGAGCCGUGGACUUGGGUUGUAAAUUUAUUUGUGGGGAGUGCGCUCCAGGAAGAGCCACCAUCCCUGCCCCCGUUUUCCCACCGGGGAGUCUGUACAGAGAUUUUUCUACGUUUUUAUUUUUUGCCUCAGAGGGAUGGGAUUGGGGAGGAGGGGAUGGGCAGCGGAGGGUUGGGGGCAUGGUCUGCAGGCUCAUCUGUGUCCGCCUUUCACUCCACUAAUGCUGUCUCAGUGUUUUCUCUCUCUCUCUUUCGAGCUUGCACUCCGGUACCCGACCCGGCGCCCUGGCCCAUCCCAUGCCGGGGGGCCAGUGGAAAGAAGACAGGCCGUCCAGCCCGUGCCCGCCUGCGGCGGGGGCACCCAGCAAGCCCGCCCACCGCCCGCUGCCUCACCUGCUUCGCCACAGACUCUUGUUCCCAGCCCCUUGGGGCCUCCGUGUUUGGGGUGGGGGAGCUGCUUAGAGACUGUGCCCGUCCUCGGCCCCCCACCCUGAAGUGCCAGCACCACCAGCACCAGAUCCUCCGCCGCCACACCGCACUGAGGACACGCCGGCCGGGCCGCCUCGUCUCAAGUUGUAUAAAGUUGUCUCCGUGUCCCCUCCUCCCUCUGCCCCCAGUGUUUCUUCUGAUUUUUUUUUCCCCUUUCCCUCCCUCCCUCUCCGCAUUCUUCCCUUGGUUCAGCACAGGUAAAACGGUUCCCCUCCCUCCCUGCCUUCAUGGAUCACCAGCUCACGUCAUGUUGCCUUCUCUUUUCUUUGUGUGUGUGUUUAUUUAAGUUAUUUUUCUUCCUCCUCUCCCUUUUCUUUUUGGCCCUCCCUCCCUCCCUCUUCUGCCAUGUAACUGGAGGAUGUGCUAUGAGUUUGCAAACAGCUGGACUGUCAGGCUGCUUUUUUUCCAGAUGUUCCUCCUCUGCCUCCCCUUCCCCUCCUCUCCCCUCCUUUUCCUUCCUUCCUUCCUUUCCUUGGAGCACUGAGCACCAUUUGGAAGCUUGAGAGAAACCAAAAUUAAAGAGAGAAAGAGAGAG